AAAGCGUUGUUGGCCCGGUUGCUCUGGAGCCGGGUCUCGGGUCUGGUGGCUGCCGGCCCUGCGGCAUCUCGCCAUGGGGAGCACGGAGAGCAGCGAGGGCCGCAGGGUGUCCUUCGGAGUGGACGAGGAGGAGCGGGUCCGGGUGCUGCAGGGUGUCCGGCUGUCUGAAAACGUGGUGAACCGCAUGAAGGAGCCCAGCUCUCCACCCCCUGCUCCCACAUCUUCUACCUUUGGCCUUCAAGAUGGCAACUUGAGAGCCCCUCACAAAGAAUCCACACUGCCCAGGUCGGGGAGCAGUGGUGGCCAGCAGCCCUCAGGGAUGAAGGAGGGUGUCAAGAGGUAUGAACAGGAGCAUGCUGCUAUCCAGGAUAAGCUCUUCCAGGUGGCAAAGAGGGAAAGAGAGGCUGCCACCAAGCACUCCAAGGCAUCCCUGCCCACGGGCGAAGGCAGCAUCAGCCAUGAGGAGCAGAAGUCAGUCCGGCUGCAGGCCAGGGAGCUGGAGAGCAGAGAGGCAGAGCUAAGACGCCGUGACACCUUCUACAAGGAGCAGCUGGAGCGUAUUGAGAGGAAGAAUGCUGAGAUGUAUAAACUGUCUUCAGAGCAAUUCCAUGAGGCAGCCUCAAAGAUGGAGAGCACAAUAAAGCCCCGCAGGGUGGAGCCCGUCUGCUCAGGGUUGCAGGCCCAGAUUCUCCACUGCUACCGAGAUCGCCCGCAUGAGGUGCUGCUGUGCUCGGACCUGGUCAAGGCAUACCAGCGCUGCGUGAGCGCCGCCCACAAGGGCUGAGGAGCAGACAUCAUUCCCUGCCCUGGCAGUGACUUGGAGCCCUGAAGAAGGGACCAAUCAUGGGACCACAGCCACUGUGCCCUGCCGUUUCCUGCUGGGCCCCUGCAUAUGCCCCUGAGCCUGGGGCUGCCACGUGUUUAGGAAACAAAGUAUGCGCUACUGUCUGAAAACAAAUAAAGCAGAUGCCUUUGUUUUCAGUCGUUGACUCACUGGCAAACA